GUCACUGCGUUCGGACCCAGACCCGCUGCAGGCAGCAGCAGCCCCCGCCCGCGCAGCAGCAUGGAGCUCUGGGGGGCCUACCUCCUCCUCUGCCUCUUCUCCCUCCUGACCCAGGUCACCACCGAGCCACCAACCCAGAAGCCCAAGAAGAUUGUAAAUGCCAAGAAAGAUGUUGUGAACACAAAGAUGUUUGAGGAGCUCAAGAGCCGUCUGGACACCCUGGCCCAGGAGGUGGCCCUGCUGAAGGAGCAGCAGGCCCUGCAGACGGUCUGCCUGAAGGGGACCAAGGUGCACAUGAAAUGCUUUCUGGCCUUCACCCAGACGAAGACCUUCCACGAGGCCAGCGAGGACUGCAUCUCGCGCGGGGGCACCCUGGGCACCCCUCAGACUGGCUCGGAGAACGACGCCCUGUAUGAGUACCUGCGCCAGAGCGUGGGCAACGAGGCCGAGAUCUGGCUGGGCCUCAACGACAUGGCGGCCGAGGGCACCUGGGUGGACAUGACCGGCGCCCGCAUCGCCUACAAGAACUGGGAGACUGAGAUCACCGCGCAACCCGAUGGCGGCAAGACCGAGAACUGCGCGGUCCUGUCAGGCGCGGCCAACGGCAAGUGGUUCGACAAGCGCUGCCGCGAUCAGCUGCCCUACAUCUGCCAGUUCGGGAUCGUGUAGCCGGCGGGGCGGGGGCCGUGGGGGGCCUGGAGGAGGGCAGGGGCCGCGGGAGGCCGGGAGGAGGGUGGGGACCUUGCAGCCCCCAUCCUCUCCGUGCGCUUGGAGCCUCUUUUUGCAAAUAAAGUUGGUGCAGCUUCGCGGAGAGGA